GUCUUGCCGCGGCUCCCGGGAUGCGCGGAGGCGGUGGCGAUGGCGAUGAUGCCUCUAGUCCUGCAUCAUCCAGAGCGGCAGGCGGAGCUGGGGUCCGGACUGCGAGAUGGAGGAGGGGCGGCGCUGCGGCCACCCGGCAGGCUUAUCUGUCUUGGGCCUCUUUUGUCACAUAUUGCUCAUCUGUGAGCUGAGGCCCUGACUCACUGAGUAUUUUUGGGGAGCAGAAGAAGGAGACAUUUCUCUCCGAAAAUGAACUCAACAGGCCACCUUCAGGAUGCCCCCAAUGCCACCUCGCUCCAUGUGCCUCACUCACAGGAAGGAAACAGCACCUCUCUCCAGGAGGGUCUUCAGGAUCUCAUCCACACAGCCACCUUGGUGACCUGUACUUUUCUACUGGCGGUCAUCUUCUGCCUGGGUUCCUAUGGCAACUUCAUUGUCUUCUUGUCCUUCUUCGAUCCAGCCUUCAGGAAAUUCAGAACCAACUUUGAUUUCAUGAUCCUGAACCUGUCCUUCUGUGACCUCUUCAUUUGUGGAGUGACAGCCCCCAUGUUCACCUUUGUGUUAUUCUUCAGCUCAGCCAGUAGUAUCCCGGAUGCUUUCUGCUUCACUUUCCAUCUCACCAGUUCAGGCUUCAUCAUCAUGUCUCUGAAGACAGUGGCAGUGAUCGCCCUGCACCGGCUCCGGAUGGUGUUGGGGAAACAGCCUAAUCGCACGGCCUCCUUUCCCUGCACCGUACUCCUCACCCUGCUUCUCUGGGCCACCAGUUUCACCCUUGCCACCUUGGCUACCUUGAAAACCAGCAAGUCCCACCUCUGUCUUCCCAUGUCCAGUCUGAUUGCUGGAAAAGGGAAAGCCAUUUUGUCUCUCUAUGUGGUCGACUUCACCUUCUGUGUUGCUGUGGUCUCUGUCUCUUACAUCAUGAUUGCUCAGACCCUGCGGAAGAACGCUCAAGUCAGAAAGUGCCCCCCUGUAAUCACAGUCGAUGCUUCCAGACCACAGCCUUUCAUGGGGGUCCCUGUGCAGGGAGGUGGAGAUCCCAUCCAGUGUGCCAUGCCGGCUCUGUAUAGGAACCAGAAUUACAACAAACUGCAGCACGUUCAGACCCGUGGAUAUACCAAGAGUCCCAACCAACUGGUCACCCCUGCAGCAAGCCGACUCCAGCUCGUAUCAGCCAUCAACCUCUCCACUGCCAAGGAUUCCAAAGCCGUGGUCACCUGUGUGAUCAUUGUGCUGUCAGUCCUGGUGUGCUGUCUUCCACUGGGGAUUUCCUUGGUACAGGUGGUUCUCUCCAGCAAUGGGAGCUUCAUUCUUUACCAGUUUGAAUUGUUUGGAUUUACUCUUAUAUUUUUCAAGUCAGGAUUAAACCCUUUUAUAUAUUCUCGGAACAGUGCAGGGCUGAGAAGGAAAGUGCUCUGGUGCCUCCAAUACAUAGGCCUGGGUUUUUUCUGCUGCAAACAAAAGACUCGACUUCGAGCCAUGGGAAAAGGGAACCUCGAAGUCAACAGAAACAAAUCCUCCCAUCAUGAAACAAACUCUGCCUACAUGUUAUCUCCAAAGCCACAGAAGAAAUUUGUGGACCAGGCUUGUGGCCCAAGUCAUUCAAAAGAAAGUAUGGUGAGUCCCAAGAUCUCUGCUGGACAUCAACACUGUGGUCAGAGCAGCUCGACCCCCAUCAACACUCGGAUUGAACCUUACUACAGCAUCUAUAACAGCAGCCCUUCCCAGGAGGAGAGCAGCCCAUGUAACUUACAGCCAGUAAACUCUUUUGGAUUUGCCAAUUCAUAUAUUGCCAUGCAUUAUCACACCACUAAUGACUUAGUGCAGGAAUAUGACAGCACUUCAGCCAAGCAGAUUCCAGUCCCCUCCGUUUAAAGUCAUGGAGGCUAUAGGAUCUUAUGUAAACAGUUUUUGUUUCUGAUAGUAAUGGACUUUAUUCUAACUUGAGAUCAGUGGCGGAUCAAAACCUACAAGAUUCAACUGAAAAGUUGGCAGUUAUGGUUUUCUUUCAUCUGAUGUGUCAGUAUCUGUUGAUUUGCUUUGUAGUUUGUUGACAUCUUAAGAUUUGAUGUGAAAGUUUUAGAUUUUUUACCCUGC